GCACUCUGGGGGAACAUGGCCGCUUCCGGUCUCCCUCCCGGGCCGGCGCUGGCCUGACUGCGGCCCCGGUCCGUAGCACUCCGCCCUCCGCUUCUCCCGCCCUGUAGCCGCGAAGACUGCUUCAGCCUUUCCCUGUGCUGCCCCUGCCGCGCGAUGGAGAAGAGCUCGAGCUGCGAGAGUCUUGGCUCCCAGCCGGCGGCGGCUCGGCCGCCCAGCGUGGACUCCUUGUCCAGUUAAUGUGUUAAGAGCCAUUGACAUUUGAAGAUCAUCAGAAGUGAAGAUAAAACAUCUCAAAAAUUAUAAUUGCCUCCACUUCUCAUUCAGAGAAUUCAGUGCAUACAAAAUCAGCUUCUGUUGUAUCAUCAGAUUCCAUUUCAACUUCUGCCGACAACUUUUCUCCUGAUUUGAGGCCCAUGCAGUCCAGUUCGGGAGCUAAGUCACUUAAACACUGUGUGAUAGUUCCUACACAUCUCAUUAUAGUUUAGGGAGUCUCGCUCUAUCCCCUAGGCUGGAGUGCAUUGGCGCCAUCUCGGCUCAUUUGCAACCUCUGUCUCCCGGGUUCAAGCGAUUCUCCUGCCUCAGCUUCCCGAGGAGCUGGGAUUACAGGUCCUGAGGGAGUCUAACAAGUUAGCAGAAAUGGAAGAACCACCCUUGCUUCCAGGAGAAAAUAUUAAAGACAUGGCCAAAGAUGUAACUUAUAUAUGUCCAUUCACUGGCGCUGUACGAGGAACUCUGACUGUCACGAAUUAUAGGUUAUAUUUCAAAAGCAUGGAACGGGAUCCCCCAUUUGUUUUAGAUGCUUCCCUUGGUGUGAUAAAUAGAGUAGAAAAAAUUGGUGGUGCUUCUAGUCGAGGUGAAAAUUCUUAUGGACUAGAAACUGUGUGUAAGGAUAUUAGGAAUUUACGAUUUGCUCAUAAACCUGAGGGGCGGACAAGAAGAUCCAUAUUUGAGAAUCUAAUGAAAUAUGCAUUUCCUGUCUCUAAUAACCUGCCUCUUUUUGCUUUUGAAUACAAAGAAGUAUUCCCUGAAAAUGGGUGGAAGCUAUAUGACCCUCUUUUAGAGUAUAGAAGGCAGGGAAUUCCAAAUGAAAGCUGGAGAAUAACAAAGAUAAAUGAACGAUAUGAACUUUGUGAUACAUACCCUGCCCUCCUGGUUGUGCCAGCAAAUAUUCCUGAUGAAGAAUUAAAGAGAGUGGCAUCCUUCAGAUCAAGAGGCCGUAUCCCAGUUUUAUCAUGGAUUCAUCCUGAAAGUCAAGCCACAAUCACUCGGUGUAGCCAGCCCAUGGUUGGAGUGAGUGGAAAGCGAAGCAAAGAAGAUGAAAAAUACCUUCAAGCUAUCAUGGAUUCCAAUGCCCAGUCUCACAAAAUCUUUAUAUUUGAUGCCCGGCCAAGUGUUAAUGCUGUUGCCAACAAGGCAAAGGGUGGAGGUUAUGAAAGUGAAGAUGCCUAUCAAAAUGCUGAACUAGUUUUCCUGGAUAUCCACAAUAUUCAUGUUAUGAGAGAAUCAUUACGAAAACUUAAGGAGAUUGUGUACCCCAACAUUGAGGAAACCCACUGGUUGUCUAACUUGGAAUCUACUCAUUGGCUAGAACAUAUUAAGCUUAUUCUUGCAGGGGCUCUUAGGAUUGCUGACAAGGUAGAGUCAGGGAAGACGUCUGUGGUAGUGCAUUGCAGUGAUGGUUGGGAUCGCACAGCUCAGCUCACUUCCCUUGCCAUGCUCAUGUUGGAUGGAUACUAUCGAACCAUCCGAGGAUUUGAAGUCCUUGUGGAGAAAGAAUGGCUAAGUUUUGGACAUCGAUUUCAACUAAGAGUUGGCCAUGGAGAUAAGAACCAUGCAGAUGCAGACAGAUCGCCUGUUUUUCUUCAAUUUAUUGACUGUGUCUGGCAGAUGACAAGACAGUUUCCUACCGCAUUUGAAUUCAAUGAGUAUUUUCUCAUUACCAUUUUGGACCACCUAUACAGCUGCUUAUUCGGAACAUUCCUCUGUAAUAGUGAACAACAGAGAGGAAAAGAGAAUCUUCCUAAAAGGACUGUGUCACUGUGGUCUUACAUAAACAGCCAGCUGGAAGACUUCACUAAUCCUCUCUAUGGGAGCUAUUCCAAUCAUGUCCUUUAUCCAGUAGCCAGCAUGCGCCACCUAGAGCUCUGGGUGGGAUAUUACAUAAGGUGGAAUCCACGGAUGAAACCACAGGAACCUAUUCACAACAGAUACAAAGAACUUCUUGCUAAACGAGCAGAGCUUCAGAAAAAAGUAGAGGAACUACAGAGAGAGAUUUCUAACCGAUCAACCUCAUCCUCAGAGAGAGCCAGCUCUCCUGCACAGUGUGUCACUCCUGUCCAAACUGUUGUAUAAAGGACUGUAAGAUCAGGGGCAUCAUUGCUAUACACUCUUGAUUACACUGGCAGCUCUAUGAGUAGAAAGUCUUCGGAAUUUAGAACCCAUCUAUGAGAGAAAGUUCAGUCACUUUAUUUAUUUUAAAUCUCUCUAGGAUGAGUUUAGAACUGUAGCAGUGCAGGUGGCUUAAGUGAAGUAACUCCAUAUGUAAUUACAUGAUUAUGAUACUAAUCUUUUAAGUAUCCAAAGAAUAUUAAAAUACUUCAAUCCUGGAUUCACAGUGGGAACAAGUUUCUAUUAAAAGGCAAAUGCUGUUACAAAUUUUUGGCAUCUGGUAAUAUUAAAACCAUUUUAGAAAUACACUCUGUGCUCACUGUGCAGAGGAACAUCAGUUUUCAAACCAACACUGAAAUUCUGUGGCAUCACAUAUAUUGGGCCUUGAUGUCAUGACAGAUCAAAAUCAUUUGAUAUCCCUUUCUCCAUUCUAGGUUUUUCUUUUUUUCAGUAACUGAUUUACCUUGAUCACUUUUCAACUUCCAUAUUCUUCAUAUAGUAAAAGGCAAAGUGUUGAAGAUACUACGGUGUGGUAGUAGUUGAAAAUUAUUGCCGUCAUUAUUUACAUACUUAAGACAUAUUAGCAAGUUGAUCCAAAAUGGGAGGCCUUAUAGAUGUGCUUGGGGGAAAAUGAAGGGGAGAAAGUAGCCAUACAGGAGUUCAAAGAAUUCCAUGCCCUUCAGAUUAGCCCAAUUACCAGAAACAUCAUGAAAGAUAUUUUAAAAACUAAUUAUUUACUACAGUGUAUUUCACUUGUCUUGUGUGUCUGAACACACAGAAGCUAAUUAGCAAGUUUUUAAGAAGUAUUUAAAAAUCUUACUAGGAUUGACAUUUUUUCUGAAUUCUGUAUAAAUAGCUUAUAGUGAGAAGUACUGUGCUCAAAUUUUACAUUUUUUUCCUUUGCAAAUUCUGUAAUUUCACUCAACGAUUAAGUCUACCAAAGAACACACUGCAUGUAAAAGAUGUAUUACAAUCUCAAAGCCAGUAAAAGAAAUCUUGCUUCACUGUUCACCUGCUACAAGUAAGAGUUUGGUGCUGGUAGAAACAUUUGACUCUGAUGUCUAUUUUAUUCUACAUAAGAGCCAUAUGUAAUGUACUGUAACAAAGGAGCUUCUUGUCCCCUUGGUCUUUUAAUUAAAAGAAAUUCCAACUGACUUUUAAACUUUGUUCUUGUCCAAAGUUGCCAUUUCUUUUUUUUCCCCAGAAAUAUUUGGAAAUUAUUGGAGGAAUAUGCACCCCAGAUGAAAAUGUUCAGUUUGUACCCAUUUUUCCUUAACCAACACCCAAAUCAAACAAUUAAAAUAUACAGUGUUUUUCCACUCACUAAUUCACUAUACAGAGAGUCUGAACCUUAGCCUCCCUCUUGGUCUUGCAGUGAGGAAGUUUCUAUUAGUAUAUCCAAUUUAGCAAAAUUGGUACCAAAAUGAUUUCUUUGGUAAUUGUGUGAAAUAUAAGCUUUUUAACAGGGCAUUUAAGUGGCUAGCAAAUCAGUAAUUAAAAAUUAAGCUUUCUACUCCAAGUAUUUCACAAACGCAUCUGCCAUUUUCCUCAUUUAAACCUUGGUUAUCUUGGCCUGAUACCACAUAAAAGAAUGUAGAAUGGCUGAAGAGAUCAAGAAUUUAAAGCUUCUAGUCUUAACAUACUUGCAUCCACUUCAAAUUCAAAUCAAAAGCCAGGGAAAUCUAAGUGCAACCCUACCACUUCUCUGCUGAGAACCUUCCAGUGGUUCCCCUCACCUUCUGCAGAAGUCUCCAAUAUGGAGUACAUGCACUUGGGCAUUUAAUAUAUACCACUGGUGUGUGUGGGAGGGAGGGAGGAGGAAUACUAGCCCUUUUUAUAUAUUUACACAAGCAAAACUUUUAAAUAUUUGAAUUGACAGUUACAUGUUUCAUAACUUUGUAUGUCUAUUGGUUGUGCAGGUGUAAUUUUUUCCCUUUUUGAUUAGGGUUACAAAAUUUAGAGACCAGUAUGAUUAAGUUGAAGCUCCUUAGCCUCCUUCGACCUAGUCUCUGCAUACCUCAACUUUUACGUACCAAUGCUACUCUGCUGUUCACAAUUGCCUCAUGUAAUCUGCAGAUUCCUGCCUCCCCACUUUGGUUCAGUCUGUCUUGUGCACCUGGAACAACUGUUCUCCCUUGUGACUAAUUCCUAUUUUCUAGAGUUUAGGCAUCAUCUCUUCCUUUGGGAAGUUAUCUGAUUCACGACUGCCUUCUCUGACAUCCCCACCUUCCUCUGUGCCCCCAUAGCACUGUGUAUACCGCUACUACCACUGCAAUUCACAUUAUAUUGGAAUGAACAAUUCACAUGUCUACCACAAGUCUGUAAACAUAACCUUAUUUGAAAUGAAUUGCAAUAAAGCUCUGUUACAACGUAA